AGAGGUGGGGCUAGGGCCCUGGUUCCCACUGCCUGGUUUCUGGGCCCCCGGCAUCCGAGUCGGCCAAAAGCCGGGCAGAAGAGAGCGCCAAGGACUGGCAGUUCCGGAACGGGCAAUCCCAGCCGAGGGGACCAGCGGCAGAGCACGGGUCCGAGCCGGGGACGGCGGCGUCGGUGGGUCAUGCUCCGGCACUCCCCCUCGCUGUGGGAGCUGGUGGAGGAGCACGUUCCGCUCCGGGAGCGACGCGAAGUGAAGAGGAUUCUGGGGGAGGCGGCGGUGGACCUGAGCCUGGAGCUGCGGGCGGAGGUGGCGAUGUUACGGGCACUGCUCCAAGAGGCUCGAUCCUCUCAAGCCCCCAGCUCCCGCCCCAUCUCUGACCCCUCUUCUCUUCUGGCACCACCGCCUCUCCUAAAGGACCUCUUGCGCCAGGAGCUCCGGCAGUUGCUCCAGGGUCUCCGCCACAAAGCCAUCUGUGAGGGCAGGGACCAGGCCCAAGCUUGGGUCCAGUAUAGCCCCAGGGUCCUGCACUUUGCCUUGGAGGAGCCCAGGUGUGAUUUGCCAGAACAGGAGAUAUUCCAGAUGAGAGGUGGUGGGCCCAGCAGCGGUCACAGAGAUCUCAGCAUCAUCAAGGACCAACUGAACGUGUCCAACAUUGACCAGGUGGCCAGACACCUGAGGGGCCUUCUGGAGGAGGAGUGUCACACCUUGGAGAGGGAGAUCCUCAUCCUGCAGCGCUGCCUGGAAGAGGAGUAUUUGAGGCCUUGCCACCCCUCUGAGGCAGCCCUGGAGCCCACCCUGGCAGAGCUAAAGGAACAGAAGAAGGCCAUGGAGCAGGAGCUGCAGGCAUCUGUGGGGCCUUCUUGUGUCUCUCCCAACCACAGGCAGCGGCCCUUGGGGUCCUCCACACAGGGCCUCAGACCCCCGCUUCCCCUCUGCGGGGUUGCACCUCUCCAGUGCUGCCUGCCUGCACCUCCUCUGGAGCCCUACCUUCGACCUCGAGGCCAGUCGGCUACCCACCGCUGGGGACGGCAGCUUCAGUGCAGCCCCAGGGAAGGGCCAGCUUCCACACCCAUGUCCAGUGCAGCACCCCAAGCCCCAGCCUGAAGGGCUGGUCACCGAGUAGGCUCUGGCUUCUGCCACAGCGCACCUGUCUGCCGCUGCCGCCUCAGCUGCUUUGGCCCAGCCAGCUUCAGAUCUGGUCUUGGCGAGCUCUCGCCAGGACCCCAAGGCUGUUGGUCUGUCUGGCCCUUGCCCCACCCCCUUGCCAGAUCCCUGGUGUCUGGAGCUGAGUGGCCGGGCAUCGGUCCCAAGCAUCAAAGCCUUUGGCCUUUCUCCUCCCAGGCCUCCACAAAGGCCUGGCAGACAGAGGUCUCAUUCCAGCCUGACUCUUGUCCCCUGGGGGACCCAGACAAAGCACAGCAGCCGCUCAGAGACAGGAAUAGAAAUUUCAUUAAAAUCUAUGGACUUUAAAA